AUCUGUCAUCUCACUACCACCAUGCUGGCCUCAGGGCUGCUUCUGGUGGCCUUGCUGGCCUGCCUGACUGUGAUGGUCUUGAUGUCUGUCUGGCAGCAGAGGAAGAGCAGGGGGAAGCUGCCUCCGGGACCCACCCCACUGCCCUUCAUUGGAAACUACCUCCAGCUGAACACAGAGCACAUAUGUGACUCCAUCAUGAAGUUCAGUGAGUGCUAUGGCCCCGUGUUCACCAUUCACUUGGGGCCCCGGCGGGUCGUGGUGCUGUGUGGACAUGAUGCCGUCAGGGAGGCUCUGGUGGACCAGGCUGAGGAGUUCAGCGGGCGAGGCGAGCAAGCCACCUUCGACUGGGUCUUCAAAGGCUAUGGCGUGGCGUUCAGCAACGGGGAGCGCGCCAAGCAGCUCCUGCGCUUUGCCAUCGCCACCCUGAGGGACUUCGGGGUGGGCAAGCGAGGCAUCGAGGAGCGCAUCCAGGAGGAGUCGGGCUUCCUCAUCGAGGCCAUCCGGAGCACGCACGGCGCCAAUAUCGAUCCCACCUUCUUCCUGAGCCGCACAGUCUCCAAUGUCAUCAGCUCCAUUGUCUUUGGGGACCGCUUUGACUAUGAGGACAAAGAGUUCCUGUCACUGCUGAGCAUGAUGCUAGGAAUCUUCCAGUUCACGUCAACCUCCACGGGGCAGCUCUAUGAGAUGUUCUCUUCGGUGAUGAAACACCUGCCAGGACCACAGCAACAGGCCUUUAAGUUGCUGCAAGGGCUGGAGGACUUCAUAGCCAAGAAGGUGGAGCACAACCAGCGCACGCUGGAUCCCAAUUCCCCACAGGACUUCAUCGACUCCUUUCUCAUCCACAUGCAGGAGGAGGAGAAGAACCCCAACACGGAGUUCUACUUGAAGAACCUGAUGAUGAGCACGUUGAACCUCUUCAUUGCAGGCACCGAGACGGUCAGCACCACCCUGCGCUAUGGCUUCUUGCUGCUCAUGAAGCACCCAGAGGUGGAGGCCAAGGUCCAUGAGGAGAUUGACAGAGUGAUCGGCAAGAACCGGCAGCCCAAGUUUGAGGACCGGACCAAGAUGCCCUACAUGGAGGCAGUGAUCCACGAGAUCCAAAGAUUUGGAGACGUGAUCCCCAUGAGUUUGGCCCGCAGGGUUAAAAAGGACACCAAGUUUCGGGAUUUUUUCCUCCCUAAGGUGCUAUCCUCCCCACCCCCUAGACUACGGGGACUUCCAGCCCUUCUCUGUGUCCCCAGAAUCCUGCCCCCAUUAGAAGCUUUCUACUCACUGUCCCACUCCCUCAAUCAGUCAAAAAGGACUUCCCCAACCACCACAUCCAUUCCACCUUUCCACUUAGACACUCCUGAGUCCUGCAUCUCCCCAGACUCUUUGUGUCGGGAGAAUCAAACUCAAGUUCCAAAACUUCCUAUCUUAAGAAACAGAAGCCCCCUUUCCAUUAGGCCUUUUGUCUUAGGGACACAAAUUUCAGGUCCCCCAAACAACCUGCGUAGCAAGACAUGGACCCCAUGUCUCCCAAACUUCCUGUUUCAGAGAUGUGAACCUUCUAUUCCCCAAAGCUCCUCCUUCACAGGACCCCAACUCCUCCAUGCCUGCCACUUCCCCUUACCUGGGGCACACUAGUUCCCCCUCCAGCCCCUGUGUACUUUCACCAAUCCCCCGACCCUCCUCAUCACACACAACUUCCUCCUCCCUACCAGGGCACCGAAGUGUUCCCUAUGCUGGGCUCCGUGCUGAGAGACCCCAGCUUCUUCUCCAACCCUCAGGACUUCAAUCCCCAGCAUUUCCUGGAU